AGUAGCGGCUGUGUAUCGGCGAUGCGGGUGUUUCCCCAGUUUGUGGCCCCUGAGUGCUGGGUGGGACCGCGGUGACUGAACCUAGAAGGUGGAGAGGAAUCGUCCUCGGUGCCCAGAGGCGGCUCUGCAGCCCCGUGACGGCGACCACUGCUCCCGGGCCGUGCUUCCCCAAGUAGUCCGAUGGCAGCGGCUGUGCCGAGGCGCCCAACUCAGCAGGGCACUGUGACCUUUGAAGAUGUGGCUGUGAACUUUUCCCAGGAGGAGUGGUGUCUUCUUAGUGAGGCUCAGAGGUGCUUGUACCGUGAUGUGAUGCUAGAGAACCUGGCUCUCAUAUCCUCGCUGGGUUGUUGGUGUGGAUCAAAAGAUGAGGAGGCACCUUGUAAGCAGAGAAUUUCUGUACAAAGAGAGUCUCAGAGCAGGACUCCUAGGGCAGGUGUUUCUCCUAAGAAGGCUCACCCCUGUGAAAUGUGUGGCCUCAUCUUGGAGGAUGUUUUUCACUUUGCUGACCACCAGGAAACUCAUCACAAGCAGAAGCUGAACAGGAGUGGAGCAUGUGGAAAAAACUUGGAUGACACUGCAUACCUUCAUCAGCACCAGAAGCAGCAUAUUGGAGAGAAAUUCUACAGAAAGAGUGUCAGAGAAGCAUCGUUUGUAAAGAAACGUAAGCUCAGGGUGUCACAGGAGCCAUUUGUCUUCCGCGAGUUUGGGAAGGACGUUCUGCCCAGUUCAGGAUUGUGCCAAGAAGAAGCUGCUGUAGAGAAGACAGACAGUGAAACUAUGCAUGGCCCACCCUUUCAGGAGGGAAAAACUAAUUACAGUUGUGGAAAACGCACAAAAGCCUUCAGCACCAAACACUCAGUUAUUCCACACCAGAAACUUUUCACUAGAGAUGGAUGUUAUGUGUGCAGUGAUUGUGGAAAAUCCUUUAGCAGAUAUGUCAGCUUCAGUAAUCAUCAGCGAGAUCACACUGCAAAAGGACCUUAUGAUUGUGGAGAGUGUGGGAAAUCUUAUAGUCGAAAGAGCAGCCUUAUUCAACAUCAGCGAGUCCACACUGGACAGACAGCUUAUCCCUGUGAGGAGUGCGGGAAAUCUUUUAGUCAGAAGGGCAGCCUUAUUAGCCAUCAGCUUGUUCACACUGGAGAAGGGCCUUAUGAGUGUAGAGAAUGUGGGAAAUCUUUUGGUCAAAAGGGUAACCUCAUUCAACAUCAGCAAGGUCACACUGGAGAGAGAGCUUAUCACUGUGGGGAAUGUGGGAAAUCUUUUCGUCAGAAGUUCUGCUUUAUUAACCAUCAGCGUGUUCACACUGGAGAAAGGCCUUACAAGUGUGGAGAAUGUGGGAAAUCUUUUGGUCAAAAGGGCAACCUCGUUCACCAUCAGCGAGGUCAUACUGGAGAAAGGCCCUAUGAGUGCAAGGAAUGUGGGAAAUCAUUUAGGUACAGAUCCCACCUCACUGAACACCAGAGACUUCACACUGGGGAAAGACCUUACAAUUGUAGGGAAUGUGGGAAAUUAUUUAACAGGAAGUAUCAUCUUCUGGUUCAUGAGAGAGUUCACACUGGAGAAAGGCCAUAUGCGUGUGAGGUAUGUGGGAAAUUAUUUGGCAAUAAGCACAGCGUGACUAUACAUCAGAGGAUUCACACUGGAGAAAGGCCGUAUGAAUGCAGUGAAUGUGGGAAAUCAUUUCUUUCCAGCUCUGCGCUUCAUGUUCAUAAAAGAGUUCAUUCUGGACAAAAGCCUUAUAAGUGCAGUGAAUGUGGAAAAUCCUUUUCUGAAUGUUCCAGUCUCAUUAAACACAGGAGAAUUCACACUGGAGAAAGGCCUUAUGAAUGCACCAAAUGUGGAAAAACAUUUCAGCGAAGCUCUACCCUCCUUCAUCAUCAGAGUUCACACAGGAGAAAGGCCUUAUGAGUGCAGUGAAUAUGGGAAAUCGUUUGCUGAAGCAUCCCGUCUCGUUAAACACAGGAGAGUUCAUACUGGAGAAAGGCCUUAUGAGUGCUGUCAAUGUGGAAAACAUCAGAAUGUCUGCUGUCCUCGGUCUUAAGCGACUUCGUGUUGAGAUGGAGUCUUGUUCUGUCACCCAGGCUGGAGUGCAGUGGUGCAGUCUUGGCUCGCUGCAACUUGGGCCUCCUGGGUUCAUGCAAUCCUCCUACCUCAGCCUCCUGAGUAGCUGGGAUUAUGAGUACACACCACCACGCCCAGCUAAUUUUUGUGUUUUUAGUGGAGAUGGGGUUUUACCAUGUUGGCCAGGCUGGUCUCAAACUCCUGACCUCAAGUGAUCCACCCACCUUGACUCCCAAAGUGCUGAAAUUACAGGCAUGAGCCUCUGCACCUGGCCUUCAUUCUUUUCGUAUUGCUUAGAAUAUGACAUGCUGAACCAGGCAUGGUGGCUCAUGCUUGUAAACCUGAUGCUUUGGGAGGACAAGGUGGUUCAUUGGAGGCCAGGAGUUAGAGAUCAGCCUGGGCAACAUAGCCAGACCUCCUCUCUACAAAAAGAAAAAAGAAUGACAUGCUUCUUGUUUUUGUCUGUUAUAAAUGAAACUGCUAUAUUUGAAUGCAGUUGUUCAUGUAGGUAUGUUUCACUAUGGUAAUAUGGUGGUGUGCAGUGCCUGAGUCACGUGAUAGAUUAAAGUACAACUCUUUUUUGAGACAGAGUCUCACUCUGUCACCCAGGCGGGAGUUAGGUGGCAUGAUUUCGGCUCACUGCAACCUCUGCCUCCCAAGUUCAACUGAUUCUUCUGCCUCAGCCUCCCGAGUAGCAGGGAUUACCGGUGUGCACCACCAUGCCUGGAUAACUUUUUUUUUUAUUUCUAUUAGCAAUGGGGUUUCACCAUGCUGGCCAGGCUUGUUAUGAACUGACCUCAAGUGAUCUGCCUGCCUCAGCUUCUCAGGUGUGACCUACUGUGCUUGGCCUAAUGUACAACUUUUUAAGCAAUGCCAAACUAUGACUUAAGAAUGAAAUUAUUGCUCAUUUGUAUAUCUAUCUACCAUCAGUGUCCAAGAAUUUCUGUUCUAUCUUACCAAGAGGGAGUAUGGUUAGUAUUUGAAAUUGUUUAUUAUUUUAAUAAGUGGUUAUAACUUUUGAGUCAGUGGUUUAUGUUUUGCAUUUUUUUUGUUUUGAGACAAAGUCUCGCUCUGUCUCCCAGGCUAGAGUACCGUGGCACAAUCUCAGCUCAUUGCAACCUCUGCUUCCUGGGCUCAAGCACUCUGCCCACCUCAGCCUCCAGAGUAGCUGGAAAUACAGGUAUGCACCACCACAACUGGAUAACUUUUGUAUUUUCUGUAGAGAGGGUUUUACCUUUUUGCCCAGUCUGAUCGCGAACUCCUGGGCUCAGGCGAUCCACUUGCCUAGGCUCCAAAAGUGCUUGGUCUACAGGGGUGAGGCACCCUGCCUGGCCUCACCUGUAGGCUUGUUUUUUAAAAUGAAUUUUAUCUAUUUCCCAUUUCAUUAAUAUAUUUAAAAAUAAUGAAAUAACAAAGACGUAUGUUGGACUUCAUUCAUUCUUCAGUGAUGUCACUUUGCUGCAAGGAAUAUUUGGUUUUCUUUUUUUUUUUUUUUUCCAGAUGGAGUCUAGCUCUGUCUCCUAAGCUACAGUGAAGUGGCAUGAUCUCGGCCCACUGCAACCUCCACCUCCUGUGUUCAAGCGAUUCUGCCUCAGCCUCCUGAGUAGCUGGGACUACAGGCAUGUGCCAUUAUACCUGGCUAAUUUUAUUUAUUUAUUUUAGUAGAGAUGGGGUUUCACCAUGUUACCCAGGCUGCUCUCUACCUUCUGAGCUCAAGUGAUCCACCUGCCUCGGCCUCCCAAAGUGCUGGGAUUACAGGUGUCAGCCACUGUACCUGGCUGAAUACUUGGUUUUCAGUACCACAAGAACUAUGAGCUGGUUAUCCACUUCAUGUGGAAUCAUAAGCGUCCCAAAGUGACAAUACAUAUAGAUUGCCAGGCAGUGAAACAGUUAAGAUGCCACCAUAGCUUUCUUUUCAACAUCUUUCUAAGAUUACCUUACUAUUUCUUUUGUUCCAAGUUUGUACUUCCUCACAGUUCUCACAUAUGGAAAGGAUACACACUUUGUAGAAACAAGAACUUUAUGUUAUCCAAGUUCUAGGAUAGCCAUGAGCUCCAAUUAUCUCAGAGCUCUGAGUCCUCUACUCAAUACCCAUUGAGAUUUAUGUGUUCUGAGGCUUUUGUCUUCUAGCUACUUACUUCAUUCUCCAUGGGUAACGUCAUUCAUCCACAUUAACUAAUUUCCUCACUCCAAGCUCUUUUCUAGAGAUAAUCUCCAGUCCCUGUGCAGAAACUGUCAUUGCACUUUCUGCUGAAAUGGCAGUUUCUUCUCAGCAAGGUGAGAUUAUGGAAUCCAGAAUCUUUUUUCAGGGGUCACAUGCCCAUUUCCCCACUUGCAUGAAUGUCGACACUGCAGCCACAGUUUUGGCCGUAAAUGUGAAUUUGGCAAGUAACCACUGUUCCCAGGGAAAUGUCCCAAUCAGAAGAAGAUUAUCUGGGACACUGAUACUGACAGGGAGAUGGGACAUUCUGAGGGACCCGGAGGCAGGGUGCCACCUCCUCAACUUCCCUGAGGGCUGCCUAGAAUCUGUUUCCUCUCACUCUGAAUUAUUCUUCCUCUUAUGGCUGACCAAAAACAUGGAACCUCACAAAGUCCACUGUAACAGCUUUAUAUUUGUGAAGUGAAGAACAUGAAGACAGUUUCAAGCAAAGUUAUUGAGUGGACACUUUGUGUUUUUUUUGAGAAGUCUCACUCUUUCACCCAGGCUGGAGUGCAGUGGCACGAUCUCGGCUCACUGCAACUCCACCUCCCGGGUUCACGCCAUUCUCUUGCCUCAGCCUCCUGAGUAGCUGGGACCACAAGCGCCCACCACGUCAGCUUAAUUUUUUUGUUUUGUUUCUUGAGACAGAGUCUUGCUCUCUUGCCCAGGUUGGAGUGCCGUGUCGCAAUCUCAGCUCACUGCAACUUCUACCUCCUGGAUUCAAGCACUUCUCCUUGCCUCAGCCACCUCUUUAGCUGGGAUUACAGGUGCGUGCCACCACACCCAGCUAAUUUUUGUAUUUUUAGCAGAGACCAGGUUUCACCAUGUUGGUCAGGCUGGUCUCAAACUCCUGACCUCGUGAUCCACCCACCUCGGCCUCCCAAAGUGCUGGAAUUACAGGCGUGAGCCACUGCACCUGGCCUGUAUUCUUUUCUUUAGUAGAGACGGGGUUUUACUGUAUUUGCCAGGAUGGUCUCGAUCUCCAGACCUCGUGAUCCGCCCGCCUUAGCCUCCCAAAGUGCUGGGAUUAUAGGCGUGAGCCAACACGCCCUGGCCACUUCUUGUCUUUGCAACAUUUUUUAGAUAUGUAUUUGUGUUUUUUGGGGAGCUUAAUUUGCUAAUGGAAUCUCUGUUAUUUUCCUAACAUGCUUGGUGGAUACAAGAGUUAAGACUUCCUGUCCCGUUUAGUGUAACAAAAGAAAGUUAAGAAAUGUGGAUAAAAGAUUGUAAGUUAGAAAUGGCAAGAUAAUCAGCUAUAUGAAGAAUCUUGGCCAGGUGUGGUGGCUGAGGCCUGUAAUCCCACCACUUUGGGAGGCUGAGGUGGGCGGAUCACAAGGUCAGGAGUUCAAGACCACCCUGGCCAAUAUUGUGAAUUCCUGUCUCUACUAAAAAUACAAAAAUUAGUCGGGCAUGGUGGCGGGUGCCUGUAGUCCCAGCUACUCGGGAGGCUGAGGCCAGAAAAUCGGUUGAACCUGGGAGGUGGAAGGUGCACUGAGCCAAUAUCACACCAGUGCACUCCAACCUGGUGACAGAGAGACACAUCAUCUCAAAAAAAAAAAAAAAACUCAAUCCAUAAAUGUUAUACUUUAUAACUUUAUAACAGCAUGUUAUAUGGGCUUAGAUAUUAUCCCUAAAUUUUUUUUUUUUUUUUUUUUUUUGAGACAGAGUCUCACUCUGUCACCCAGGCUGAAGUGCAAUGGCAUGGUCUCGGCUCACUGCAACCUCCGCCUCCCAGGUUCAAGUGAUUCUCUUGCCUCAGCCUCCCGAGUAGCUGGGCCUAUAGGUUCCCUCCACCACGCCCAGCUAAUUUUUGUAUUUUUAGUAGAGAUGGGCUUUCACUACGUUAGCCAGGCUGGUCUCAAACUCCUGACCUCAUGAUCCACCCCCCUCGGCCUCCUAAAGUGCUGGGAUUACAGGCAUCUGCCACCGCACUCGGCUUAUCCCUAGAAAUCCUAUGAUAGCAUGAUGUAUAGGCACCUAAAGGCAUGGCACUUGAGAAAUGUGAAUAAGAUUGUAAGUUACAAAUAGCAAGGUACAGUCAGAUGUUAACAGUCUCAGCCCCUAAAUGUCACCUUGUAUUACAGCAUGUUAUAUAAGCACAUACAGGCACAUACAUGAAAUAGUGAUACUUCAUUCUCAGUAAUAUCUUCAUCCUUCUCACUGGAAAGAUCUUUGAUGAUUUUUAAUCAACAUAGGAGUUUCAAUGAUAUCUAGAAGUUUAAAAGGGCUCGUUCAAACAAAUUAUGACCACACACACUGAAGAGUAUGUUUGUCUCUUGUGGUGUAAAUUUUUUUUUAUUACACCAAAUUAUGUUCACACAAAACCUUUGUAAUCAGGGGGAAUUAAAGAGCCUUCCUGGAAAAUGGAGGUUGCAAUCAGCCGAGAUGGUGCCAUCGCACUCUAGCCUGGGGAAUAGAGUGAGAUCCUGCCUCAAAAAAAACAAAAAAAUUCUUUAUUUUCUCCAUAAACUACAGUUUAUAUAAGCAAAAGUUUCAGUACUAAGCAAUUUUAGUCUCUGCAGUCUCUUGUCUUGAAUUAAUACAACUUUUGUUAAUUCUCUUAUGAAGUUAAUCUUCCUGCUUGUAUGUGAAUUAAAUAUAUGUCAAACUUUUUUUGUACAAAA